CUUUUCCGUUGUCCCUUCGCGCCCCAAACCACAUCCUGGAGCGCACUCUCCAGCGUGGCUGGCAGCGGGGACGGUGCGCCGGGGCGCAGGCCCAAGAGUCGCGUGCGCGGCCCCUUGCACCAUCCCCCCGGGCCCACCCCCGGGCCGCGCUGAUUGGGCAGGUAGGGACUCUGCCCAGCGGAAAGUUUUGGGUGCCGGGAGGAAGUCUAACCUUUGGGAGACUCCAAGACAGCAGCUCCGAGGUCGGCGGGGGUCUGGGUGGCCAUGGAGGAGCCCCCUGUGCGAGAAGAGGAAGAGGAGGAGGGAGAGGAGGACGAGGAGAGGGACGAGGUUGGGCCCGAGGGGGCGCUGGGCAAGAGCCCCUUCCAGCUGACCGCCGAGGACGUGUAUGACAUCUCCUACCUGUUGGGCCGCGAGCUUAUGGCCCUGGGCAGCGACCCCCGGGUGACGCAGCUGCAGUUCAAAGUCGUCCGCGUCCUGGAGAUGCUGGAGGCGCUGGUGAAUGAGGGCAGCCUGGCGCUGGAGGAGCUGAAGAUGGAGAGGGACCACCUCAGGAAGGAGGUGGAGGGGCUGCGGAGACAGAGCCCUCCGGCCAGCGGGGAGGUGAACCUGGGCCCAAACAAAAUGGUGGUUGACCUGACAGAUCCCAACCGACCCCGCUUCACUCUGCAGGAGCUAAGGGAUGUGCUGCAGGAACGCAACAAACUCAAGUCGCAGCUCCUGGUGGUGCAGGAAGAGCUGCAGUGCUACAAGAGUGGCCUGAUUCCACCAAGAGAAGGCCCAGGAGGAAGAAGAGAAAAAGAUGCUGUGGUUACUAGUGCCAAAAAUGCUGGCAGGAACAAGGAGGAGAAGACAAUCAUAAAAAAGCUGUCUGCAGCUUCACUCCUGAAGCUAGGGAGACCAGGAGCCCACCAGGAGGAACGAGCAACUCCAGACGCGCCGCCUUAAGAGCUGUAACACUCACCACGAAGGUCUGCAGCUUCACUCCUGAGCCAGCGAGAUCACGAACCCACCAGAAGGAAGAAACUCCGAACACAUCUGAACAUCAGAAGGAACAAACUCUGGACACGCCACCUUUAAGAACUGUAACACUCACCGCGAGGGUCCGCGGCUUCAUUCUUGAAGUCAGUGAGACCAAGAACCCACCAAUUCCGGACACACUGGGAUUACAGGCGUGAGCCACCGCACCCGGCUUUUUUUUGGGGGGUGGUGGGGACGGAGUCUUGCUCUAUCGCCCAGGCUGGAGUGCAGUGGCACCAUCUGGGUUCACUGCAAUCUCUGCCUCCCAGAUUCAAGCGAUGCUCCUGCCUCAGCCUCCCGACUAGCUGGGACUAUAGGUAUAUGCCACCACACUGGGUUAAUUUUUGUAUUUUUGUAGAGACGGGGUUUCACCAUAUUGGCCAGGCUGGUCUCGAACUCCUGACCUCAUGAUCCGCCCUCCUCGGCCUCCCAAAGUGCUGGGAUUACAGGCGUGAGUCACCGUGCCCGGCCAGUUUAUAGGUUUAGAAACUGAAACUCUGGCUGUGGAGCUAGGAAGCAGCUUGCCCAGGAGGCAAAUGCAGGCCUGAUUCCAAGGCCCGGGCGCGGAGCUGCCAAGCUUUAUGGGUCCAGAGUCACUGGCAAGUCCUAAUAAUAGUAAUAAUUUACUGUAUGCCUCGCCUGCAUCAUUCUAAGUACCUUUCCGAUGCUGUCUCACAUACUUUUGUGGGAUGGGUAUCACUAUUGUCCUUGGGGUCCUCCCAAGGAGGUUAAGGCAUAAUGGGUGAAAAGUCUUGUCUAAGGUCCUCAGCUAGAAAGUGGUAGAAGCAGGACUUGAGCCCAGAUACAAAGUCCACACACAGGCUUCAACCACUCUGCCUUCCAGGAAGAGCUGGUAGUGUUUAAGAGUCUAGUCCAGAACACUGUCUCAACAGCAUCAUUAGAUCAGGGCUCCUAAUCCCUAGAACCCUGUGUAACACUGCAACCCUGGCCAGGCAUAGUGGUUCAAGCCUGUAAUUCCAGCACUUUUGGAGGCCAAGGUGAGAGGAUUGCUUGAGCCCAGGAGUUCGAGACCAGCCUAGGCAACAUAGUAAGAACCUAUCUUUACAAAAAACAAAAAAUUAGCCAGGCAUGGUGGUGAGCACCUGUAGUCCCAGCUCCUGGGGAGGCUGAGGCGGGAAGAUUAAUUGAGCCCGGGAGUUUGAGGCUGCAGUGAGCUAUGAUCACACCACUACACUCCAGCCUGGGUGACAGAGUGAGACCCUGUCUCCAAAUAUAUAAAUGCUCCCCUGCCUCCCUGUGGGGAUAGAUAGGGUAAGAGAACCCACUCAGAAAGAAAGGUUAAGAUGGCCUGGGUGGCUGUGGUACCCCAGGAGACUAAAAAAAGUUACGGUGAGAAAUGCUUGGACUGCAACUCUUGGUAAAAUCUGAUGCUGGCAGGUGGGCAUUUUGGAAAAUAAGUCCUUGGGGUGAUUCUCCUAGAGAUGGGCCUAGCUUGACAACAGGUAACAGAGCUGUGACGUCAGCUGAGCUCUGGCGGUUCUCACACUGCAGGAUUCCAACUACAAACCUAGACCGGGGAGGAACAGGCUCAGAAGUAGGUUUUCGCCGGGUGCAGUGGCUCAUGCUUGUAAUCCUAGCACUUUGGGAGGCCGAGGUGGGUGGAUCACAAGGUCAGGAGUUCGAGACCAGCCUGGCCAAGAAGGUGAAACCCUGUCUCUACUAAAAAUACAAAAAUUAGCUAUUCAGGAGGCCAAGGCAGGGGAAUUGCUUGAACCUGGAUGGCAGAGGUUGCAGUGAGCUGAGUUCAUGCCACUGCACUCCAGCCUGGGCGACAGAAUGAGACUCCGUCUCAAAAAAAAAAAAAAAAAAAAAAAGGUUUUCAAGCCAAGUCUCAGAAGGCACAGGAGGUGGUUGCUGUAGCAAUCAUCUUUUAUUUUAUUUAUUUGAGACAGAGUCUCGCUCUGUCGCCCAGGCCGGAGUGCAGUGGCAGGAUCUCAGCUCCUGACCUCAUAAUCCGCCUGCCUCGCCCUCCCAAAGUGGUGGGAUUACAGGGAUUACCGUGCCUGGCCAGCAGUCAUCUUUUACAAUGAACAAAUAGGGCUGGGCGCGGUGGCUCACAUCUGUAAUCCUAGCACUUUGGGAGAUGGGCAGAUCACGAGGUCAGGAGACCAGCCUGGCCAACAUGGUGAAACCUCGUCUCUACUAAAAAUACAAAAAUUAGCUGGGUGUGGUGAUGCACGCCUGUAAUCCUAGCUACUCAGGAGGUUGAGGCAGGAGAAUCGCUUGAACCCGGGAGGUGGAGGUUUCAGUGAGCUGAGAUUGCACCACUGCACUCCAGCCUGGGCGACAGACAGACCAAGACUCCAUCUCAAAAAAAAAAUAAAUAAAUAAAUAAAAAUAAGUCAGGCACAGUGGCUCACGCAUGCCUGUAAUCACAGCCCUGUGGGAGGGUGAGGCAUGAGGAUCGCUUGAGGCCAGGGGUUUGAGACUAGCUUGGGCAACAUAGUGAGACCCUAUCUCUACAAAAAGUAAAAUGAACAAAUAAAUAUAGCAACUACAUAUCAGAACUUGGAGGCACUUAUUAGCUAUUAGUCCUGAGUACUUGUAAACACUGAAUAGAAGCUAGCCAAAUUUUUAAUUCUAAUAAUAGCUAAUACUGAUUACUGAAGGCUAUGUGCAAGGCACUGUUCCAAGUGUUGUUUUUUUUUUUUUUGUAUUAACUCAUUAAAUCCUCACAAUCACCCUGUA